AAUGAGCCUGACCCCUUCAAGCGCCGGCGGACGCAGCAGUCCGGACCCAGGCGCGCCCCUCCCGCCCCAGCCCACCCCGGCCUGCCGCCCGGGAGGGGAACAUGCCGCGCUCCUUCCUGGUGAAAACGCACUCCAGCCACAGGGUCCCCAACUACCGGCGGCUGGAGACGCAGAGAGAAAUCAAUGGUGCCUGCUCUGCCUGUGGGGGGCUGGUGGUGCCCCUCCUCCCCCGAGACAAGGAGGCCCCUUCUGUGCCCGGUGACCUUCCCCAGCCCUGGGACCGCUCCUCGGCCGUCGCCUGCAUCUCCCUGCCCCUCCUGCCACGGAUCGAGGAAGCUCUGGGGGCCUCUGGGCUGGACGCCUUGGAAGUCAGCGAGGUCGACCCUCGGGCCAGCCGGGCCGCCAUUGUACCCCUCAAAGACAGCCUGAACCACCUCAACCUGCCCCCACUGCUGGUGCUGCCCACACGGUGGUCCCCGACCUUGGGCCCAGACCGGCACGGGGCUCCGGAAAAACUGCUUGGGGCUGAGCGGAUGCCCCGAGCCCCGGGCGGCUUUGAGUGCUUCCACUGCCACAAACCCUACCACACGCUGGCCGGGCUGGCCAGGCACCGGCAGCUGCACUGCCACCUGCAGGUGGGGCGUGUCUUCACCUGCAAGUACUGCGACAAGGAGUACACCAGCCUGGGUGCCCUCAAGAUGCACAUCCGCACUCACACGCUGCCCUGCACCUGCAAGAUCUGUGGCAAGGCCUUCUCCAGGCCCUGGUUACUGCAGGGCCAUGUCCGCACCCACACAGGGGAGAAGCCCUAUGCCUGCUCGCACUGCAGCAGGGCCUUUGCCGACCGCUCCAACCUUCGGGCCCAUCUGCAAACGCACUCAGACGCCAAGAAGUACCGGUGCCGGCGCUGCACCAAGACCUUCUCCCGCAUGUCCCUCCUGGCGCGGCAUGAGGAGUCUGGCUGCUGCCCGGGCCCCUGAGAGGCACGUGGUCGGCGCAGGUAGGAGGGAUGGUCCUCACCGGGAGAGCUGGCGUCCCUCCUGCCCCCAGAGGAGCCAGGAGUCUGGGAGGGCGGGGCCUGGCCUCACACUUGGUGCGUCCUCCACAUCUGCGUCCAAUCAGAACCAAAGAAGUCCAGCGGGGGCCACUGGGCCGGAGGACACUCCCCCAGGCAUCCCACCGCGCGGAGCCCACUCAGAGGAGACUCCUCUCCCGGGGAAGGCUUUCAUCAGAACAAGAGCCAUGGUUCCAUUUCGACACGGCCAGGUCUCCGGGGCUACCCUUCCAAGAGUCAGAGCCUCGGGGAGGUGGCCGCCAGCAUGGGCCGGCACUGCCGCCGGAUGGCUGGCAAGGCUGCCUAGUUCCAUUGCAGCAGAAAUGAACAGUUCUGACUUAUAGUGAGCACCGCCCUGUGGCCCUUCCUCAGUAGGCACAACUACCUCUCAGCCAGCCCCCGCCAGCCUUUGGUUUGGGGUCUGGGACGAGCUGCCCCAUGUCACACGUCUAUGUGCAUGUGCACACACACUCAAACAUGUACACACACGUGCCCUCCCCACCUCACUAGACUCUCCGGGAGAUGGGGCAGGACUGGGAGAGCCCACGAUUGGUGAUUUGGGUGUGUUGGGAUGAGGCGGAGUGCCUGUGGGAUUUGUCCCGGUCAGAGCCUCAGGGGGCUGGGGUCUCAGGGCACUCAGCUUCCCAGGCAAUAACAGCCGUGGGGUAAUAAAUGGUCUCUGCACA